GUGCGAGCUCAGAUCAGCGUGGGGUGGAGGAGAAGUGGAGUUUGGAAGUUCAGGGGCACAGGGGCACAGGCCCACGACUGCAGCGGGAUGGACCAGUACUGCAUCCUGGGCCGCAUCGGGGAGGGCGCCCACGGCAUCGUCUUCAAGGCCAAGCACGUGGAGCCGAGGGUGGGCUGGCAGUGUCUGCCUUCUAUCCUGCAGACUGGCGAGAUAGUUGCCCUCAAGAAGGUGGCCCUAAGGCGGUUGGAGGACGGCUUCCCUAACCAGGCCCUGCGGGAGAUUAAGGCUCUGCAGGAGAUGGAGGACAAUCAGUAUGUGGUACAACUGAAGGCUGUGUUCCCACACGGUGGAGGCUUUGUGCUGGCCUUUGAGUUCAUGCUGUCGGAUCUGGCCGAGGUGGUGCGCCAUGCCCAGAGGCCACUAGCCCAGGCACAGGUCAAGAGCUACCUGCAGAUGCUGCUCAAGGGUGUCGCCUUCUGCCAUGCCAACAACAUUGUACAUCGGGACCUGAAACCUGCCAACCUGCUCAUCAGCGCCUCAGGCCAGCUCAAGAUAGCGGACUUUGGCCUGGCUCGAGUCUUUUCCCCAGACGGCAGCCGCCUCUACACACACCAGGUGGCCACCAGCCCUCUUCCUCGCAGGUGGUACCGAGCCCCCGAGCUCCUGUAUGGUGCCCGCCAGUAUGACCAGGGCGUCGAUCUGUGGUCUGUGGGCUGCAUCAUGGGGGAGCUGUUGAAUGGGUCCCCCCUUUUCCCGGGCAAGAACGAUAUUGAACAGCUUUGCUAUGUGCUUCGCAUCUUGGGCACCCCAAACCCUCAAGUCUGGCCGGAGCUCACUGAGCUGCCGGACUACAACAAGAUCUCCUUUAAGGAGCAGGUGCCCAUGCCCCUGGAGGAGGUGCUGCCUGACGUCUCUCCCCAGGCAUUGGAUCUGCUGGGUCAAUUCCUUCUCUACCCUCCUCACCAGCGCAUCGCAGCUUCCAAGAUGUCGUAUGCUUGGGUGCCAUCACCUCAUGACGCUGCCUGCUGUUGUGCCCUGUGCUCACUCCUCUCCAGCCCCAGGGGCUCUCCUCCAUCAGUACUUCUUCACAGCUCCCCUGCCUGCCCAUCCAUCUGAGCUGCCGAUUCCUCAGCGUCUAGGGGGACCUGCCCCCAAGGCCCAUCCAGGGCCCCCCCACAUCCAUGACUUCCACGUGGACCGGCCUCUUGAGGAGUCGCUGUUGAACCCAGAGCUGAUUCGGCCCUUCAUCCUGGAGGGGUGAGAAGUUGGCCCUGGUCCCGUCUGCCUGCUCCUCAGGACCACUCAGUCCACCUGUUCCUCUGCCACCUGCCUGGCUUCACCCUCCAAGGCCUCCCCAUGGCCACAGUGGGCCCACACCACACCCUGCCCCUUAGCCCUUGCGAGGGUUGGUCUCGAGGCAGAGGUCAUGUUCCCAGCCAAGAGUAUGAGAACAUCCAGUCGAGCAGAGGAGAUUCAUGGCCUGUGCUCGGUGAGCCUUACCUUCUGUGUGCUACUGACGUACCCAUCAGGACAGUGAGCUCUGCUGCCAGUCAAGGCCUGCAUAUGCAGAAUGACGAUGCCUGCCUUGGUGCUGCUUCCCCGAGUGCUGCCUCCUGGUCAAGGAGAAGUGCAGAGAGUAAGGUGUCCUUAUGUUGGAAACUCAAGUGGAAGGAAGAUUUGGUUUGGUUUUAUUCUCAGAGCCAUUAAACACUAGUUCAGUAUGUGAGAUAUAGAUUCUAAAAACCUCAGGUGGCUCUGCCUUAUGUCUGUUCCUCCUUCAUUUCUCUCAAGGGAAAUGGCUAAGGUGGCAUUGUCUCAUGGCUCUCGUUUUUGGGGUCAUGGGGAGGGUAGCACCAGGCAUAGCCACUUUUGCCCUGAGGGACUCCUGUGUACUUCACAUCACUGAGCACUCAUUUAGAAGUGAGGGAGACAGAAGUCUAGGCCCAGGGAUGGCUCCAGUUGGGGAUCCAGCAGGAGACCCUCUGCACAUGAGGCUGGUUUACCAACAUCUACUCCCUCAGGAUGAGCGUGAGCCAGAAGCAGCUGUGUAUUUAAGGAAACAAGCGUUCCUGGAAUUAAUUUAUAAAUUUAAUAAAUCCCAAUAUAAUCCCAGCUAGUGCUUUUUCCUUAUUAUAAUUUGAUAAGGUGAUUAUAAAAGAUACAUGGAAGGAAGUGGAACCAGAUGCAGAAGAGGAAAUGAUGGAAGGACUUACGGUAUCAGAUACCAAUAUUUAAAAGUUUGUAUAAUAAUAAAGAGUAUGAUUGUGGUUCAAGGAUAAAAA